ACACUCGCCGCGCGCGCGGCGGCCGGGCUGGACCUUGCUGGCCCGCGGCGCCAUGAGCCGCAGCCUGGACUCGGCGCGGAGCUUCCUGGAGCGGCUGGAAGCGCGGGGCGGCCGGGAGGGGGCAGUCCUCGCCGGCGAGUUCAGCGACAUCCAGGCCUGCUCGGCCGCCUGGAAGGCUGACGGCGUGUGCUCCACCGUGGCCGGCAGUCGGCCAGAGAACGUGAGGAAGAACCGCUACAAAGACGUGCUGCCUUAUGAUCAGACGCGAGUAAUCCUCUCCCUGCUCCAGGAAGAGGGACACAGCGACUACAUUAAUGGCAACUUCAUCCGGGGCGUGGAUGGAAGCCUGGCCUACAUUGCCACGCAAGGACCCUUGCCUCACACCCUGCUAGACUUCUGGAGACUGGUCUGGGAGUUUGGGGUCAAGGUGAUCCUGAUGGCCUGUCGAGAGAUAGAGAAUGGGCGGAAAAGGUGUGAGCGGUACUGGGCCCAGGAGCAGGAGCCACUGCAGACUGGGCUUUUCUGCAUCACUCUGAUAAAGGAGAAGUGGCUGAAUGAGGACAUCAUGCUCAGGACCCUCAAGGUCACAUUCCAGAAGGAGUCCCGUUCUGUGUACCAGCUACAGUAUAUGUCCUGGCCAGACCGUGGGGUCCCCAGCAGUCCUGACCACAUGCUCGCCAUGGUGGAGGAAGCCCGUCGCCUCCAGGGAUCUGGCCCUGAACCCCUCUGUGUCCACUGCAGUGCGGGUUGUGGGCGAACAGGCGUCCUGUGCACCGUGGAUUAUGUGAGGCAGCUGCUCCUGACCCAGAUGAUCCCACCUGACUUCAGUCUCUUUGAUGUGGUCCUUAAGAUGAGGAAGCAGCGGCCUGCGGCCGUGCAGACAGAGGAGCAGUACAGGUUCCUGUACCACACGGUGGCUCAGAUGUUCUGCUCCACACUCCAGAAUGCCAGCCCCCACUACCAGAACAUCAAAGAGAAUUGUGCCCCACUCUACGACGAUGCCCUCUUCCUCCGGACUCCCCAGGCACUUCUCGCCAUACCCCGCCCACCAGGAGGGGUCCUCAGGAGCAUCUCUGUGCCCGGGUCCCCGGGCCACGCCAUGGCUGACACCUACGCGGUGGUGCAGAAGCGCGGGGCUCCAGCGGGCGCCGGGAGUGGGACGCAGACGGGGACGGGGACGGGGACGGGGGCGCGCAGCGCGGAGGAGGCGCCGCUCUACAGCAAGGUGACGCCGCGCGCCCAGCGACCCGGGGCGCACGCGGAGGACGCGAGGGGGACGCUGCCUGGCCGCGUUCCUGCUGACCAAAGUCCUGCCGGAUCUGGCGCCUACGAGGACGUGGCGGGUGGAGCUCAGACCGGUGGGCUAGGUUUCAACCUGCGCAUUGGGAGGCCGAAGGGUCCCCGGGACCCGCCUGCUGAGUGGACCCGGGUGUAAGUCUAACGCCAGUUCCUGCCUGUUGCCUCUUGUGAGCUCGGACUGCUGAUGCCCCGGUGCUGCUGAGCGCCGUGCGCAGAAUGGAAACAGUGGGCCUGGAUCAAAGUUAAAGUUUCUCAGGGUGGGAAAUGUGGGGGCUUUGCCCCAAUGACUGUAGCAUUCAAGGCUUGAGGCUGGAGGAGGUAGCUAGGGUAUAGUGGCUGGUGAGGCUGCACAGAGCAGAUUCAAGAAAGAAGAUCAGGAAGGGGCAUGACCCCUGAGUUAUGAAGGGGAGAAGGGACAGAUGAGCUUCCGGAGACUGCUCUCCUCACCACACAGCACUAGUCCAUCCUCAGCACCUGAGCCUCCCUCACUUGGACACUCAGGGGACCACACAGAGAAGUGGAUGGACACUUCGCCAUCCAGGCAGAACUAAGCCAGGCAUAACCACAGCCAAGCAGAUUAACCCCAGGCAGACCGAUAAAAAGACCUCCAGAUAGGCAGACAGACAGAUGGACCACCAACCUGGACAGACAGCCAAAGCUUCAGAGAUACAGUCCACAGGUGGACAAAGGGAUCCCCAGCCAGAGAGAGAGAGACCAGCCAACAGCUUGAUAGACCAGUGCAGCCAGAGAGACCACCAAACAGAGCCCCCAAAAGACAGACAUCUCUGCUAGCUGGACAGCCAGGUGGACCCCCUAAGUUAGAUUACUAGACAGAUAUAAACAGAUCCCCUGCUGAACAGAUACACAGAGUUCUCAGACCCCACCCCCACCCUCAGGUGGGCUGGCUGGCUGACAGACCUUCUGGCCAGACAGACUCCUAACCAACCAGAUGGACUGCCAGACAGGCAGACAUCAGCCACAUGGAAUCCUGACAUCCCAGCCAGCCGGCCAGACUCUCAUCUUGAUGUCUUGAUGGAUGGACCCCAGCUAGUCAGACAUGAUCCUCCAGAUUGACAGACAAGUCCCCCAAAUGAGUACACAUCUCCAGCUAUUCAGACAGAUGGACCCCCAGCAAAUCAGGACCUAUCUAGGCAGACCCCAGCCAGACCCCCGCCAGACAGACUCCCAACCAGACUGACCCCUUACUAUUCACACAGCCUGCCGAGUAGCUGGGACUACAGGUCUAAUUUUUUUUUUUUUUAAGAAAUGAGUUUUUGCCAUGUUGCCCAGACUGGUCUUGAACUCCCAACCUCAAGCAAUCCUCCUGCCUCAGCCUCCCAAAGUGCUGAGAUUACAGGUGUGAGCCACCAGGCUCAGCCCCCUAAGAUUUGAAACACUUUAAAUGGCCCAUGGUAGGGUUCCUGCUAGGAUAAAACAUUAAGCGGCUGUUAAAAGAAAUAAAAGGAGGACACGUCUCUGUGCACUGGUGUGGACAAAUCUCCAAGUCACUGCAAAAUGGAAAAAGUAUAAGAUGCUCUUUCCCUGAACCUCAAGGGUCCCGCCCCUCUCACUUUCAGGUCUCUGGACCUCUGACUGACACUGUGCCUGCCCAGGUCCCUGUAUGCACUGCCACAGUGCCCUGGGCCCCAUGUCCACCCCUGUCCUGCCCUUCUCUGGGAUAGGGCUGGCCUUCCUCUGCCUCUGCCUGGCUGCAUCCAUGGUCGAUCUCAAGUGCCUUGGCAUGAACUCCACUCUCCUGCAGCCUUCAAUCAAGGAAUGAUGGGGAUGUGUACAUACCCCACCCCACCCCUUGGCAGGGUGAUGCUGAGGUGUGGAUUUUUAACAGUUCCCAGACUUUCCCAGGAGGCUUGGGUUUGGGUGCCCACAGUGGGAGCUGGUGUGAUAUCAUACCUUCGCCGGCCGCCUUUCCUUCCUGUUCUCUGUGCCCCUACUCCCACUCUAGAGCUGCCCCGUUUCUCUGUUUUCGUGAAAGAGCUGACCCUGUGCUGCCUCCCACUCUCCCAAUGCCCCUGCCACUCCUGUGAGCCUGCUGCUGGUGAGGUCGGUGCUGACCUCUGUGUUGCUGGAUAAUGAGUCAUCUAUCUCUGGAGGAGAAGAAAGGCAGGUCCUCCACAGCCCUGAUAAAAUCUCCAAGUCUCCCAGUUUCGGGUCCCUCUCCUGGGAUGCAGACCCACUGCCUGCCCAGCUGGUACGAUCCACAUGCCCUCUUCUUGGGAAUAGGGGCAUGGGAAAGUGACUAAAGAUACUGUUCUGGCUGCUGUGUUCACUGUGAGUAAUAAACUGUCCAUUUCUCCGA